GCCGCCGCCGCACUUCCGGGUGCCAUUGCAGGUGAGCCAGGGUCUCCCGAGAACCUCACCCCCCGGUAUUCCCCUCACCCUGAAGUAAGGGAGUCUCCCUCUUCCCCUCAGCUCCUAACCAAGGUGCUCAGUACCGCGGCUAGGGUGCCCAGCGGGAGGCUGGGUAGUUACCGGAGGAGGCAGAGCCGGUCGCACGCCUGGGUCCCAGCGGAGGCCCAGUCGACUCUCGACCCGGGCCCCAGCCUCCUUGCGUGGCGAAGGUCGUGCCUCAGGUCUCCUGGCGAACCUGGCCGCCCGGAAGCGGAGAGUGACUCCUCCCCUUCGUCCCCUCGGUGCCCGCCAGGCGGCGCCGUCGGCUGGGCCCGGAUUCCCCUGCGGCUUCGAUCCCUUUCCACUGGGUAUUGAGAUUGGCGAGGGGAGAGGCGCAGAAACGGCGUGAUGCAGAAAGCCUCAGUGUUGCUCUUCCUGGCCUGGGUCUGCUUCCUCUUCUACGCUGGCAUUGCCCUCUUCACCAGUGGCUUCCUGCUCACCCGUUUGGAGCUCACCAACCAUAGCAGCUGCCAAGAGCCCCCAGGCCCUGGGUCCCUGCCAUGGGGGAGCCAAGGGAAACCUGGGGCCUGCUGGAUGGCUUCCCGAUUUUCGCGGGUUGUGUUGGUGCUGAUAGAUGCUCUGCGAUUUGACUUCGCCCAGCCCCAGCAUUCACACGUGCCUAGAGAGCCUCCUGUCUCCCUACCCUUCCUGGGCAAACUAAGCUCCUUGCAGAGGAUCCUGGAGAUUCAGCCCCACCAUGCCCGGCUCUACCGAUCUCAGGUUGACCCUCCUACCACCACCAUGCAGCGCCUCAAGGCCCUCACCACUGGCUCACUGCCUACCUUUAUUGAUGCUGGUAGUAACUUCGCCAGCCACGCCAUAGUGGAAGACAAUCUCAUUAAGCAGCUCACCAGUGCAGGAAGGCGUGUAGUCUUCAUGGGAGAUGAUACCUGGAAAGACCUUUUCCCUGGUGCUUUCUCCAAAGCUUUCUUCUUCCCAUCCUUCAAUGUCAGAGACCUAGACACAGUGGACAAUGGCAUCCUGGAACACCUCUACCCCACCAUGGACAGUGGUGAAUGGGACGUGCUGAUUGCUCACUUCCUGGGUGUGGACCACUGUGGCCACAAGCAUGGCCCUCACCACCCUGAAAUGGCCAAGAAACUUAGCCAGAUGGACCAGGUGAUCCAGGGACUUGUGGAGCGUCUGGAGAAUGACACACUGCUGGUAGUGGCUGGGGACCAUGGGAUGACCACAAAUGGAGACCAUGGAGGGGACAGUGAGCUGGAGGUCUCAGCUGCUCUCUUUCUGUAUAGCCCCACAGCAGUCUUCCCCAGCACCCCACCAGAGGAGCCAGAGGUGAUUCCUCAAGUUAGCCUUGUGCCCACGCUGGCCCUGCUGCUGGGCCUGCCCAUCCCAUUUGGGAAUAUCGGGGAAGUGAUGGCUGAGCUAUUCUCAGGGGGUGAGGACUCCCAGCCCCACUCCUCUGCUUUAGCCCAAGCCUCAGCUCUCCAUCUCAAUGCUCAGCAGGUGUCCCGAUUUCUUCAUACCUACUCAGCUGCUACUCAGGACCUUCAAGCUAAGGAGCUUCAUCAGCUGCAGAACCUCUUCUCCAAGGCCUCUGCUGACUACCAGUGGCUUCUCCAGAGCCCCAAGGGGGCUGAGGCGACACUGCCGACUGUGAUUGCUGAGCUGCAGCAGUUCCUGCGGGGAGCUCGGGCCAUGUGCAUCGAGUCUUGGGCUCGUUUCUCUCUGGUCCGCAUGGCGGGGGGUACUGCUCUCUUGGCUGCUUCCUGCUUUAUCUGCCUGCUGGCAUCUCAGUGGGCAAUAUCCCCAGGCUUUCCAUUCUGCCCUCUACUCCUGACACCUGUGGCCUGGGGCCUGGUUGGGGCCAUAGCGUAUGCUGGACUCCUGGGAACUAUUGAGCUGAAGCUAGAUCUAGUGCUUCUAGGGGCUGUGGCUGCAGUGAGCUCAUUCCUCCCUUUUCUGUGGAAAGCCUGGGCUGGCUGGGGGUCCAAGAGGCCCCUGGCAACCCUGUUUCCCAUCCCUGGGCCCGUCCUGUUACUCCUGCUGUUUCGCUUGGCUGUGUUCUUCUCUGAUAGUUUUGUUGUAGCUGAGGCCAGGGCCACCCCCUUCCUUUUGGGCUCAUUCAUCCUGCUCCUGGUUGUCCAGCUUCACUGGGAGGGCCAGCUGCUUCCACCUAAGCUACUCACAAUGCCCCGCCUUGGCACUUCAGCCACAACAAACCCCCCACGGCACAAUGGUGCAUAUGCCCUGAGGCUUGGAAUUGGGUUGCUUUUAUGUACAAGGCUAGCUGGGCUUUUUCAUCGUUGCCCUGAAGAGACACCUGUUUGCCACUCCUCUCCCUGGCUGAGUCCUCUGGCAUCCAUGGUGGGUGGUCGAGCCAAGAAUUUGUGGUAUGGAGCUUGUGUGGCGGCGCUGGUGGCCCUGUUAGCUGCCGUGCGCUUGUGGCUUCGCCGCUAUGGUAAUCUCAAGAGCCCCGAGCCACCCAUGCUCUUUGUGCGCUGGGGACUGCCCCUAAUGGCAUUGGGUACUGCUGCCUACUGGGCAUUGGCGUCGGGGGCAGAUGAGGCUCCCCCCCGUCUCCGGGUCCUGGUCUCUGGGGCAUCCAUGGUGCUGCCUCGGGCUGUAGCAGGGCUGGCUGCUUCAGGGCUCGCGCUGCUGCUCUGGAAGCCUGUGACAGUGCUGGUGAAGGCUGGGGCAGGCGCUCCAAGGACCAGGACUGUCCUCACUCCCUUCUCAGGCCCCCCCACUUCUCAAGCUGACUUGGAUUAUGUGGUCCCUCAAAUCUACCGACACAUGCAGGAGGAGUUCCGGGGCCGGUUAGAGAGGACCAAAUCUCAGGGUCCCCUGACUGUGGCUGCUUAUCAGUUGGGGAGUGUCUACUCAGCUGCUAUGGUCACAGCCCUCACCCUGUUGGCCUUCCCACUUCUGCUGUUGCAUGCGGAGCGCAUCAGCCUUGUGUUCCUGCUUCUGUUUCUGCAGAGCUUCCUUCUCCUACAUCUGCUUGCUGCUGGGAUACCCGUCACCACCCCUGGUCCUUUUACUGUGCCAUGGCAGGCAGUCUCGGCUUGGGCCCUCAUGGCCACACAGACCUUCUACUCCACAGGCCACCAGCCUGUCUUUCCAGCCAUCCAUUGGCAUGCAGCCUUCGUGGGAUUCCCAGAGGGUCAUGGCUCCUGUACUUGGCUGCCUGCUUUGCUAGUGGGAGCCAACACCUUUGCCUCCCACCUCCUCUUUGCAGUAGGUUGCCCACUGCUCCUGCUCUGGCCUUUCCUGUGUGAGAGUCAAGGGCUGCGGAAGAGACAGCAGCCCCCAGGGAAUGAAGCUGAUGCCAGAGUCAGACCCGAGGAGGAAGAGGAGCCACUGAUGGAGAUGCGGCUCCGGGAUGCGCCUCAGCACUUCUAUGCAGCACUGCUGCAGCUGGGCCUCAAGUACCUCUUUAUCCUUGGUAUUCAGAUUCUGGCCUGUGCCUUGGCAGCCUCCAUCCUUCGCAGGCAUCUCAUGGUCUGGAAAGUGUUUGCCCCUAAGUUCAUAUUUGAGGCUGUGGGCUUCAUUGUGAGCAGCGUGGGACUUCUCCUGGGCAUAGCUUUGGUGAUGAGAGUGGAUGGUGCUGUGAGCUCCUGGUUCAGGCAGCUAUUUCUGGCCCAGCAGAGGUAGCCUAGUCUGUGAUUACUGGCACUUGGCUACAGAGAGUGCUUGAGAACAGUGUAGCCUGGCCUGUACAGGUACUGGAUGAUCUGCAAGACAGGCUCAGCCAUACUCUUACUAUCAUGCAGCCAGGGGCCGCUGACAUCUAGGACUUCAUUAUUCUAUAAUUCAGGACCACAGUGGAGUAUGAUCCCUAACUCCUGAUUUGGAUGCAUCUGAGGGACAAGGGGGGCGGUCUCCGAAGUGGAAUAAAAUAGGCCGGGCGUGGUGACUUGCACCUAUAAUCCCAGCACUUUGGGAGGCAGAGGUGGGAGGAUUGCUUGGUCCCAGGAGUUCAAGACCAGCCUGUGGAACAUAACAAGACCCCGUCUCUACUAUUUAAAAAAAAGUGUAAUAAAAUGAUAAUAUAAUUA